GAAUGUCACUGCUGCUUAGCACCUAUCUGCUCUCUGGCCUGCCUCAGUGGUCUACAGCAGUUACACACAGGCAGUGGUAUCUGUGAGCAGCUCUGUGGACUCAAAGGUUUUCUCCCUGAGAGGCAUGACCCAGGCCAGCUGAUUCAUCAGAAUCAGGAUGGACGUGGUAGAGGUCGCGGGUAGUUGGUGGGCACAAGAGCGAGAGGACAUCAUUAUGAAAUACGAAAAGGGACACCGAGCUGGGCUGCCAGAGGACAAGGGGCCUAAGCCUUUUCGAAGCUACAACAACAACGUCGAUCAUUUGGGGAUUGUACAGUCCUGCCCCUCCUGGGAGUCAGCCCCACAGGAAGGCCCUUGUCCUCCCUUCCCUGUGCCUUCUCCUGGGCUGAGCCCUGAGCUGGAAAGGGACAGAGCCAGUCCUUUCUGGGGGUCGGCACCCAGGCUGGGGCCGCUCCAGGCCCCGUGCAGUUCCUCAGCUCUGCCUGGGUUGCCUUACAGUGAGACGGAGCUGCCUCCUCUGACUGCGCGGGAGGCGAAGCAAAUUCGGCGGGAGAUCAGCCGAAAGAGCAAGUGGGUGGAUAUGCUGGGAGACUGGGAGAAAUACAAAAGCAGCAGAAAGCUCAUAGAUCGAGCGUACAAGGGAAUGCCCAUGAACAUCCGGGGCCCGAUGUGGUCAGUCCUCCUGAACAUUGAGGAAAUGAAGUUGAAAAACCCCGGAAGAUACCAGAUCAUGAAGGAGAAGGGCAAGAGGUCAUCUGAGCACAUCCAGCGCAUCGACCGGGACAUAAGCGGGACAUUAAGGAAGCAUAUGUUCUUCAGGGAUCGAUACGGAACCAAGCAGCGGGAACUACUCCACAUCCUCCUGGCAUAUGAGGAGUAUAACCCGGAGGUGGGCUACUGCAGGGACCUGAGCCACAUCGCCGCCUUGUUCCUCCUCUAUCUUCCUGAGGAGGAUGCAUUCUGGGCACUGGUGCAGCUGCUGGCCAGUGAGAGGCACUCCCUGCAGGGAUUUCACAGCCCAAAUGGCGGGACCGUCCAGGGGCUCCAAGACCAACAGGAGCAUGUGGUAGCCACGUCACAAUCCAAGACCAUGGGGCAUCAGGACAAGAAAGAUCUAUGUGGGCAGUGUUCCCCGUUAGGCUGCCUCAUCCGGAUAUUGAUUGACGGGAUCUCUCUCGGGCUCACCCUGCGCCUGUGGGACGUGUAUCUGGUAGAAGGCGAACAGGCGUUGAUGCCGAUAACAAGAAUCGCCUUUAAGGUUCAGCAGAAGCGCCUCACGAAGACGUCCAGGUGUGGCCCGUGGGCACGUUUUUGCAACCGGUUCGUUGAUACCUGGGCCAGGGAUGAGGACACUGUGCUCAAGCAUCUUAGGGCCUCUAUGAAGAAACUAACAAGAAAGCAGGGGGACCUGCCACCCCCAGCCAAACCCGAGCAAGGGUCGUCGGCAUCCAGGCCUGUGCCGGCUUCACGUGGCGGGAAGACCCUCUGCAAGGGGGACAGGCAGGCCCCUCCAGGCCCACCAGCCUGGUUCCCGCGGCCCAUUUGGUCAGCUUCCCCGCCACGGGCACCUCGUUCUUCCACACCCUGUCCUGGUGGGGCUGUCCGGGAAGACACCUACCCUGUGGGCACUCAGGGUGUGCCCAGCCCGGCCCUGGCUCAGGGAGGACCUCAGGGUUCCUGGAGAUUCCUGCAGUGGAACUCCAUGCCCCGCCUCCCAACGGACCUGGACGUAGAGGGCCCUUGGUUCCGCCAUUAUGAUUUCAGACAGAGCUGCUGGGUCCGUGCCAUAUCCCAGGAGGACCAGCUGGCCCCCUGCUGGCAGGCUGAACACCCUGCGGAGCGGGUGAGAUCGGCUUUCGCUGCACCCAGCACUGAUUCCGACCAGGGCACCCCCUUCAGAGCUAGGGACGAACAGCAGUGUGCUCCCACCUCAGGGCCUUGCCUCUGCGGCCUCCACUUGGAAAGUUCUCAGUUCCCUCCAGGCUUCUAGAAGCAUCUGGGCCAGGGCUCAUGGCUGGAUAAUUUCCCUAGGCUUAACAACCCAAGCAAGCUUCGCAUCCUCGUUUUAUUUUUGGUUAAACUUAUGAAAAUGUAUUAAGAAAGAGUGCAGCUCGAGAGAGAUUCAGAGAUGGAACACACCAGACCCCAGAUCACAAAGCCAACCAUGCCCAGCCCCUCCCAGCACCCCCAGCCCCACGACCAUCGUUCUGAAUUCUGACGACACCGUGAGCCUGCCUUUGUACUUCAAACUCAUGGAAGGAUAACCACCUUCAUGUUUUGAAAUAAAUGUUUCCUGUUGAAAUGA